AUCUUCACGCCCACGCUAGGCCCUGAGCCCAGCCUCCACGUCUCGCCGCCAACUCCACAUCCUGGCUCCUAUCUCUGCCUUCCAGGCAUCUCCCAGCUGCACGCUCGGGCCCGGCUCAGAGCCCUAAGCCCUGCCUCCCGGUCCUGGCCGGGUUUCCCAGAACUGCACGGCGCCUCUCCGCCCAGGCCCAAGCGCGAGCCCCUCCUCCACACCCGAGUCCGAGCCCCGCGUCCCGGAUUCGGACCCGCCUGCCUGGGGCGGUGCUGCACCAGGUGCGGGUGUGGCAGGCGUCUCGGAGCGCCAGGUGCAGCUUCCUGGUCAAGAUGGUCGCCGCCUGCCGCUCGGUAGCCGGGCUCCUGCCACGCCGCCGCCGCUGCUUUCCCGCCCGGGCCCCGCUGCUGCGCGUCGCCCUCUGCCUCCUGUGCUGGACCCCGGCGGCUGUGCGCGCGGUCCCUGAGCUCGGGCUCUGGUUAGAGACAGUCAACGACAAAUCAGGACCUUUGAUAUUUAGGAAAACUAUGUUUAACUCUACAGAUAUCAAGUUAUCUGUUAAGUCAUUCCAUUGUUCUGGGCCUGUGAAGUUUACCAUAGUGUGGCAUUUGAAGUAUCAUACCUGUCACAAUGAGCAUUCUAAUCUGGAAGAGCUGUUCCAAAAACAUAAACUUAGUGUUGAUGAAGACUUUUGUCAUUAUUUGAAGAAUGACAACUGUUGGACAACAAAAAAUGAAAACUUAGAUUGCAACAGUGAUUCACAGGUGUUUCCCUCUUUGAAUAAUAAAGAACUAAUAAAUAUCAGAAAUGUUUCAAACCAGGAAAGAUCAAUGGAUGUUGUAGCCAGAACACAAAAAGAUGGGUUUCAUAUCUUUAUUGUUUCUAUUAAAACGGAGAAUACAGAUGCAAGCUGGAAUUUGAAUGUUUCUCUUUCUAUGAUUGGGCCUCAUGGAUAUAUCUCUGCAUCAGAUUGGCCCCUAAUGAUUUUUUACAUGGUGAUGUGUAUUGUUUAUAUAUUAUAUGGCAUACUCUGGCUGACGUGGUCUGCCUGUUAUUGGAAAGAUAUAUUAAGAAUCCAGUUCUGGAUUGCAGCUGUUAUUUUUUUGGGAAUGCUUGAAAAAGCAGUUUUUUAUAGUGAAUACCAAAACAUCAGCAACACUGGACUGUCAACCCAAGGCUUAUUGAUAUUUGCGGAGUUGAUUUCUGCGAUUAAGAGGACGUUGGCUCGCCUUCUCGUGAUCAUUGUGAGCCUGGGCUAUGGCAUUGUGAAGCCUCGUUUAGGAACAGUCAUGCACCGGGUGAUCGGACUGGGGCUUCUAUACUUAAUCUUUGCAGCUGUUGAAGGCGUGAUGAGAGUCAUUGGGGGUUCUAACCAUUUAGCUGUUGUUCUUGAUGACAUUAUUUUAGCAGUUAUUGACUCCAUUUUUGUGUGGUUCAUUUUUAUUAGUUUGGCACAAACUAUGAAGACCCUAAGGCUAAGAAAGAACACUGUGAAAUUUUCAUUAUAUAGACAUUUUAAAAAUACUCUGAUCUUUGCUGUGCUGGCUUCUAUAGUGUUUAUGGGGUGGACAACUAAGACAUUUAGAAUUGCAAAAUGCCAAUCAGAUUGGAUGGAACGCUGGGUUGACGAUGCAUUUUGGAGCUUCCUUUUUUCGCUUAUCCUUAUUGUAAUCAUGUUUUUGUGGAGACCAUCAGCAAACAAUCAGAGAUAUGCCUUCAUGCCCUUAAUAGAUGAUUCUGAUGAUGAAAUUGAGGAAUUCAUGGUAACUUCUGAAAAUUUAACCGAAGGAAUAAAAUUAAGAGCCUCAAAAUCAGUUUCCAAUGGAACAGCUAAGCCUGCCACUUCUGAGAACUUUGAUGAAGAUUUGAAGUGGGUAGAAGAAAAUAUUCCCUCUUCAUUCACAGAUGUAGCUCUUCCAGUGUUAGUGGAUUCAGAUGAGGAAAUCAUGACCAGAUCUGAAAUGGCUGAAAAAAUGUUCUCUUCAGAAAAGAUAAUGUGAUUGGAACCCGUAUAAGAAAUGUAGUUAAGCCUGAAGGACUAUCCUUCAUCAAGACUGAAAGUGAGCUUUGAUUUGAUAUUGCCUAAAAAUUUUUAUUGUGUUAUCUUGGAAGUCUGUGUAUCAAAAUGAAGAAUUCAGAUGGUAGGAGGUUCUAUAGUCCUUUUAAAGCUGACUCUUGAGUGUCAGUUGAAUAUCCAUUAAAUUGGAUUUGGAAAUAACCUGAGGAAAGUAUUAUGAUAAAGAUCUGCACAGAUGCCUCUUAGCUGAUAGGUGGCAGGCCUGUGGGUUUGGGUUCUCCCUCUUUUCUCUGGAACAUAUGACAAUUCCAGAUUAAAGAAAAAUGUUUUUUAAUAAAUACCCUUGGUCUUUCUUCUAGUCACCUUUGAGGUAGAUAUUGUGAUUUUCUGGAGUAUAGUAUAUCCGUGUCUCUGUGUCUUAGGUUUACUAGAUGCAAUAAUACUUCUCUUUGACAUUUGUACUGAAGUGAUUUGAUAUUAAGUAAAACAGUUAAUGUUUGAAUAUAGGCAUAUUUAUAGGUUUUUUCCGCUCCCCCCCAACCCACCCUUUUUAAAAAAUCUAUACAAAGCCCUUGUUUGAGUCUCAUCAUGCACAUCAAAUCAUGGAGUUAGGUCUUCUCUGAGCUCAGGGGAACACAAGUGCACAGAGAGAGAUGUCUUGAGGGUCACUACCAAAGAAUUACCCUCAUUGUCCCUCACUCAGGCCAUGUGUACAUGCGAUGCUGCUGAGUGUGCUGGGGUGGGUGGUGGCCACGUGGCUCCCCCAGAGCACUUCCUAACUGGCAAGCUGGGAGACCCAUUACUGGUGAACUUUGUGGAAAUUAGAACUGUAUCUUUUACAUAAUCUUGGCAUAUUACAUUUCAUAAUAAAAACAUACAUUUAGUUGCAUGCUACAUCACUAUUGAUUUUAUAAUUAAUUUCUUAAGCUUCAACCAUGUUUUAUACCUUAUUUCGUUACAUCAUAUAUUUGUAAUGUGUAAUAUGAAAUCUUUUGCUUUAAUGUCUUUUUUUAAAAUGUAGAAUGUUCUAAACUUGAAAGGCAAUUGAAUGUAGUAUGAUGAAAAUGUGAAUGUUUUGCUGCUUUCAUGACCAAAGAUACAGGGCUAGUGGACAUUUAGAAUAAUAAUUAAAGCUAGAGUCUUGUAUGUCUUUUCUUUGAAGGAGUUCUAACCUUGUAAAUUGAGAAUGACUUCAGAGAAUUUUGAUUAAGAAAACAUUAAAAUCUUAACCGGCACAAACACUCCAAUUUUUUUCACUGUGAAGCCGCAAGCAAUUUUUUUUCUUUUUCUUUCAAAAGCCUACCUUCUGAAUUUAUUUCUUGUUUACUCAUUUCAGAGAGGGUAGUAAAGAAGAUCUAUUUCUGGUAGUCAUAUCGCUUGAAAGGUAUUGGUAAAUGUGUUUUCAGUCGUGACCAUGUGGAAAGUGAACAGUGUUGGCAAACAUUACCGAGAAAAUCAUGCUUUUCAAGAUGCCCUUGCUUUGGGAUAUCCUUCCUAGGGAGAAAAAAAAAAAGUAGUUUAACAAUUGUGAAUUCCAUUUCUUAUUUCAGUUUCUGCUGCAGUAAUGGGUUCCCACCCACUAUAAUUCCCAGCAUUUAUGUUCUGUUGUAUUCUCCCCUUAGCCCAGUAACAUUUUUAUCUAAUACCCCAUUCCCCAAGUUUUGAGACAGAUUGACCCCCUACUCAUUAUGUGGCUCUAGUUGAAUUUUAAAAUGUGGAAUAUUGGGCUUGCAGGCAGUAGGAGCUGCAAAUCUGGUAGAGUGGGAGUGUGGAGUUAAUGGUGAGUAUGUUAAUAAAGGGAAACUGUCUCUGACAGAAUCUCAGUAAUGUUUACCAAAACAUGUCUUUCUACAGCUGGUAGGAUAAAUGAUGCUACCCUGUAGCUCAGCUACAGGCUGCAGUGCAAACUUUUCUUCCAUCCAGAGAAAGCAGAAUUCCCUCCUAGUAACCUCAUUACAAAUACUGUUACUAGAAGGGCAUGUGCUGUCUGUCACCUUCAGUAAUAUUUGUGCCAUCUCUUGAUGACUGAUGACCUGGAUCGAGUAUUUCUAUGAAGGGUCUUCUUAGGCCCCUUACAUACGCAAGAGGGGUGCUCUAGUGCCAUAGCUGUAGUUCACAGGAAGGACACCAGGAGAAGUUAUACCUAGGGCUACUGAGCAGCUCAUCAUCCCUGUUUCUGCACAGUUUCCUGAAACUGGCCAUCAGGGCCUCUGAGGCACUCAAAUCAGUUUACUUUUAGCAUGCCCCCAUCAGGGUGGGUCUCACUGUUAGUGAGGAUACGGGUCUGGUUUGAUGUUUUUCUAGGCAAAAUGCUUAAGUGUUCUGGUUAUGCCAUUCAUUCAUACGAUGUGUGAAAUUUGCUUAAAAGGGAAUUUUCAUGAUUUGAUUUAGAUUAGUAUUUAAAUAUCUGCUUUAGAUAGCAAUUAAUUUUAUUGUAAAAAUAAGGAAAAAUAUGUGAAUAUGUGAAUUUUUUAAGCCUGAGAGAUGAUAGAAUGUUCCCAUAUUUUUCUUGUAAAGAAAAUAAUAUUUUAACUUACACAUCCUGUAGAAAAUACCACCUUUUCCCCUUGUAUUACAGUACAAUGUUUACAUUACUAUACUGUCAAGCUGAAAGUAUAAAAAAUGUACAUAUACAUUUUGAGUUAUGUAUCCUUUUUUUAAAAAAAAGUUCGAGUCUGUUGCACUAGGCUGUACAUGACUAAAGUUGACAGAUGCUAUGCUAGAUUUAUAAUCACUAGUUCUGGUACUUGUGUCUUUGUAUGAUCAAAGCAUGCAAUAAGCAAUACAAAAUACCAAGCCUUAUACUUAAAAGAAGUUUAACAUAUUGGUUAAUAUACUGGUUAAUAUACUGGUUAAACAUAUUGAAUGUAUAUAAGUGGCAAAACUAGAUUUUUAAGGAAGUGUACAUUAUAAUAUUGGAGCUCAGUACUGCAUGAAGAGACUUCAUUAAAACUAAGAAAACAUUUAUUUGGGGAGAAAUUUUAGGCAUUUAAGAACUUGUAUUUUUCUAUUUUAAAAAGUUAAAUUAUUCCGUAAUUUGGAAGAAGUUUCGUUGAAUGUAGGACAUAACCGUUUGAAGGGUUUUCAUUUGAAAAAUUGAUGUAUUUUGUGCCUUAAUAUUUUGUUCUUUUAAUAAAAAUGCUCUGAAUUUGAA